ACUGGUCGUACGGUGACAAUCAGGCUCCUGUCGGCGCCUAGCGUCUGGGCAGCGUCAGCCGCUACGUCCACCUUUUCCCUGUCUCUAGGGGUUUCUCCUCGCGCCGCUGUGUUCCAGCGCCGGCUCCGAGCUGGGAGGGUGACUGAGCCCUGAGCUUGGGCCCUCCGAGAGGUGCGUUAGCUCUGGGUCUUCUUGCCCCUACGCCCGAGCCUGGCGUUCUCUCGGCCCCCUCUUAGGAACGCUAGCCCUGGGCAGAAAUUGCCUUUGUGGCUGAAGUCGGCCAGCGUCGCGUUUCCACUCUCCCGCCGAAUCUGGACCCAAGCCAGCCUUCCCUUGUGCAUCGGUAGAUAGCUUGUGUUAAGGCGCCAGCUUCUUGGAACAGAGCUCUCUGCAAAAGUCGCGCUGAAGAAUUCAUAGUCAAAAGCUGAACUUGCAGAAGUUUCUACUUCUGGAAUGAGUGUUGAAAUGAGAUCAAUUCUGACAUUCAGUUUCGCUUUUGGGAUUAUGCCUUGGACUAACUCAGCUACUCUGAUGAGCUAAAGACUGUAGUAUAUUUGAAGGAAGACACGAGGAACUGUUUUGUAUUUUGUAGGGAUAGAACAGGACCUUGAGGAGAUUAUUAUAUGAAGACUAGUUAAAGAAACUAGCCUGGAGAUGGCUUAUGUACUCUCUCCUUUGUUUUUGUUUUGUUUUUUGAGACGGAGUCUCGCUGUCGCCCACGCUGAAGUGCAGUGGCGCGGAUCUCGGCUCAUUGUAACCUCCGCCUCCCGGGUUCAAGUGAUUCUCCUCCCUCAGCCUCCGGAGUAGCUGGGACUACAGGCAUGCAUCACCACGCCUGGCUAAUUUUUUUGUGUUUUUAGUAGAGACGGGGUUUCGCCAUGUUGGGCUGGCUGGUCUCGAGCUCCUGACCUCAAAUGAUUGGCCCGCCUCGGCCUUCCAAAGUGCUGGGAUUACAGGCGUGAGCCUCCGCGCCCGGCCUCUCUCCCCUUUGUUAUGGGCCCUAAAUGACUCUAUUUCCUCCUGCAUAUCACCUGCCCGACUCCUGUAGGCAUUUGAAUUGAUGAUUCAUGAUACGGUCUUUAGAGGCUCCAGAGGAAUUUGCAAAUUAUUAUCAUCCACUAAGUGAUUGCUGAUUACCUGAGAUACAGCAGCUCAAAAAGGACAAGGUCUCUGCCUAUGGGAGUGUUGUUACAGAUCUUAUAACAGUCGGUUUAAAGCGGGGAUCUGAUGAGCUUCUUUCUUCUGGCAUCAUUAACGGACCUUUUACCAUGAAUAGUUCUACUCCUUCUACAGGUGUGUAUGCUAAUGGGAAUGACAGCAAGAAAUUUAAACGAGAUAGACCUCCCUGUUCGCCUUCCCGUGUUCUCCAUCUUCGAAAAAUUCCAUGUGAUGUCACCGAAGCAGAGAUCAUAUCAUUAGGUCUACCAUUUGGCAAAGUAACUAAUCUUUUGAUGUUGAAAGGAAAAAGCCAGGCUUUCUUAGAAAUGGCUUCUGAGGAAGCUGCCGUUACUAUGGUGAAUUAUUACACUCCUAUUACUCCUCACCUUCGAAGCCAGCCUGUUUAUAUUCAGUAUUCCAAUCACAGAGAACUUAAGACUGACAAUCUACCUAAUCAAGCUCGAGCCCAAGCUGCACUGCAGGCUGUCAGUGCCGUCCAAUCAGGAAGCCUGGCCCUUUCUGGAGGUCCUUCCAAUGAAGGCACAGUCCUACCUGGGCAGAGCCCUGUGCUUCGAAUAAUUAUUGAAAACCUCUUUUACCCUGUUACCCUGGAAGUUCUUCAUCAGAUAUUUUCUAAAUUUGGCACAGUCUUGAAGAUUAUCACCUUUACAAAGAAUAAUCAGUUUCAAGCCUUGCUUCAGUAUGCUGACCCAGUAAAUGCACAUUAUGCCAAAAUGGCUCUGGAUGGCCAGAAUAUCUAUAAUGCAUGCUGCACUCUGCGCAUUGACUUCUCCAAGCUCACCAGCCUUAAUGUGAAAUAUAAUAAUGACAAAAGCAGAGACUUCACUCGCUUAGACCUUCCUACUGGUGAUGGCCAGCCAUCCCUUGAACCCCCUAUGGCUGCUGCUUUUGGUGCACCGGGUAUAAUUUCUUCACCAUAUGCAGGGGCUGCUGGAUUUGCCCCAGCCAUUGGAUUUCCUCAAGCUACAGGUCUAUCAGUUCCAGCUGUUCCUGGAGCUCUUGGUCCUCUCACAAUCACCUCUUCUGCUGUCACUGGAAGGAUGGCCAUUCCUGGGGCUAGUGGUAUACCAGGAAAUUCUGUUCUACUCGUCACAAAUCUCAAUCCUGAUCUUAUCACACCACAUGGGCUUUUUAUCCUAUUUGGAGUCUAUGGUGAUGUACAUCGAGUGAAGAUUAUGUUUAAUAAGAAAGAAAAUGCCUUGGUUCAGAUGGCGGAUGCAAAUCAAGCUCAGCUAGCAAUGAACCAUCUAAGUGGUCAGAGACUUUAUGGGAAAGUGCUUCGUGCUACACUGUCCAAACAUCAAGCAGUACAGCUUCCUCGAGAGGGACAAGAAGACCAAGGUCUGACUAAGGAUUUCAGCAAUAGUCCUUUGCAUCGCUUUAAAAAGCCGGGCUCUAAAAACUUCCAGAAUAUCUUUCCACCAUCAGCCACUCUGCAUCUUUCCAACAUUCCCCCUUCUGUUACAGUGGAUGAUCUGAAGAACCUUUUCAUAGAAGCUGGAUGUUCAGUGAAGGCUUUUAAAUUCUUUCAGAAAGAUCGCAAAAUGGCGCUCAUUCAAUUGGGAUCUGUGGAAGAAGCAAUUCAGGCCCUCAUUGAGCUUCAUAACCAUGACCUUGGAGAAAAUCACCACCUCAGAGUUUCCUUCUCAAAAUCUACAAUCUGACUUUUCUGUGAAUUUUUCUCCUAAAACUGGACCAUAAUUUCAGUAAAACCUUCAGACAUAGACUGAAGCAGCUCAAGACCAAUUUUGCCUCUUUCACAAAAAUAACUCUGAGUUUGAUAUUCAAGUAUAUUUUAAAAAUCAAGGGAUUUUUUUUUUUUGUAUUCCCCCUGCCCCCGCCAGUCAAAGGUUUCUUUUCCCUUUUUACCAUGGUUUCUACAAAAAUAACCUUCAGGAAAAAGAAAAUCAGGAAAAAAAUUUUUUUUCAAUAAUCUUAUUCCCUAUAUUAAAUUAGAUUUGAAGAGGAUUAACGUUGUUUUAGUUUGGGUCCAGAUCAGCCUUAUACAACAUUUCUAAACUCAUUUGUACUUUUAAAAAAUUUAAACACAGACUUCUAAAAUUACUUGAUGUAAGUAAUUUAAAUCACUUAUGACCAAGUUAUUAACCUUAUGAAUCAGAAGUCUGACCCUUGUAGGAAAUUAUAUUCACAUAUAAAGUACAUCAGAUCUUUGCCAUAUAUUGAUGGUUAUUAUGCAUAAACACAUUGAGUUGUGUUGGAAGCAGAUUUAUAAACCUGCAUGUUUUCUUUGAAUGAUUUCUUUUUUUCACUGUAAGACACUCCUUUAAAUAAUGCCUAUCUUUAACUUUUUAAGACUAUUUGGAAAAAUGCAGUGUCUCAGCUGUCCCCAGGGAAAUUAAGUGGAAUUCAACUAAGAUCUGUUAAUAAGAUGUCAGAAUAACUAAUAAUUUUAUUAGGAAAAAAUCAUGUUUUAAAUUUCAAAAUGACACUUAUUUGUCAAGUAAUAUGAUCUUGGAAAAUUUUAAAGAAAAAUAAUCCUACUUAUAAACUACUUUUUUAUAAUUGUUUUCAGAAAAAAAGUUUACAGUCUUAAGGAAAAUAUUCAGGUCUAUCAUAUGGUUUGACAGAUUUUUUAAAAGUUAUUUUUGGUAAGGUCUUCUUUUAGAAAAAAAUUAAUCUCAAGGGUUUUUUGUACCACUAUAAUCUCUAAUACUUACUCAGAAUUACUGUGUAUUUACUUAAUUUCUUAUUAUGUGCCUUAUUAUGUGCUUAAGAUACAAUAGGUUAGAGUUUAAUCUAAAUAUCUUGAAAGCUAUAUUGUGGGCUUGGUAAGCAUUUUGUUUUUUCUUUCUCUGUUUUGGUAAGGAUUUAAAAUUUUUUUCAUUGCAAUUUUAAGUGGUUUUCAAUAAGUAAUAGUUUUUAUCAAAUUUUUGGUGCUUGGUGCAGAGACGGUGUGGGGAAGGGUGAAUGGUUUUGGGAAUAAUUCAGUGCACACCUGUAGGCCUCUUUACAUUGUGACUGAUAGGGGUUAUUGCAUAUCAAUUUGGGGCUGUAGAGUGCAAUCUCAGUUUCAUCUUUUUCACCCAUCAGAAUUUGUCUCAGGAUUACUUGGUUUUUCUCAGUCCUCAAGCGAGAACUUGCUUUUCUUUGUUAAUGUGACUUUCAUUACUGAGUACCCACGUAUUUGGAGUAUGAGAAGGUGGGUUAUUUCUCAUACUCUGUCCCUCUCUUUUUCAUUGAAUGUAAGAGUACAUUUUAAUGUUGCUUCAGUGAUUGUAUAAUGUAAAAUUGUUUCUUUUUAAUAAGAAACUUUGCUAUUAUUUCUUCAAUUGUUGAUCAGAAUUUUUUAAAGCAGAAUUUGUCAAAAGGGUCAUUUUUUUGUCUACCCCUUUUACACUUUUCAGAUUCUCAAAGUGUCUCAUCUCAACUUUUAAAAGAAUAAAGAAUAUCUUGCUGGGCAUGGUGGUGUGCGCCUGUGCGCCUGUAGUCCCAGCUACAGGCUGAGCCUGUAGGCAGGAGGCUACAGGCAGGAGGAUCACUUGAGCCCAGGAGUUCAAGGCUGCAGUGCGCUAUGAUCACAUUUGUGAAUAGCCACUUCACUCCAGCCCUGGAACAUAGUGUGACCCCUUCUCUUAAAAGUAAAAAUUAAGAAAAUCUCAAUCUCUUUGCUGUAUUCCAGUGAUUAAUUUGAACAUAGGGAGGUUUUUACAGAAGAAAUUUUACCAAAAAAUAGAGACUGCAAGAGAUGAUACAGAUUGUUUAAAAAGCAGAAUUCACUCACCACUGAGCAACACUUAGUUGGUAGAAUAGAAAGGAGGGAUACUAAGUUAAGACUUUUCAAAUGGAUCAGUUUGGCUGAAUAGAUAGAUAUACUCAUGUAUGUAGUUGUGGGAGUUUUUAGUUUUUUGUUUUUUUACUUAUGAAAUAAGUUUUGACCUAGACACAAGGGGUAUAUGAAGGAGGAAAAAAAUUUCUUUGCAAAAUCUCCCAAAACUUGCUUUUUUUUCCCUUCCACACAGGCACUAUUAUAAUUUUCAGUGCCAUGUUAAAUUGGAUUAUUUCAUUUACUUUAAGUUAGGAAUUACUGUGUAAUUUAUUAAUUCAUGAUUCUCAUAACAUUCAGCAUAAGUGUAGCAAAGUUGCUAAUAACGGAAGGGGAUCAUAGUGGUGUUGAAUGUAACUUUGAAGUAGGGAAUGGCCUUUUAAGUCUGAGAGAGAACAUUUGAAUCCUUUUCAGGGAUUUGUGUAGGGGUGUGUUUGUGUGUGUGUGUGAAUGUGUGUGUGUGUAGAUAAGUGUAUAUACAUAAAUACACUCUUCUAAAGUUGUAUAUACAUAUGCACAUUACAUACAUUUUAAUUUAUUGACAAAAUUAACCAAAUUAAGAUUUGGAGAUGUGGGAUGUUCUUGUUUUAAAAUAGCAUGUUUGAAACCAUCAGUUUGUGUCUAAAAUUAGCUGUAGCACAUGGAUGUUGUCCAUAUUAAGCUAUUUGCUGUUUGAAUUAUAGAGGUCUACAGUAUUUGUGUUGGCAUAGUUUUUGUAAAAAAAAGAUUAAAAAAUAUCAGGAUGGUGGAAAAACUAGAUCUGUGUAUCUCUGUUUUGGCAUGCAUUUAUUCAGUAUCUUCUAGCAAUGGUUUUUCUCUGUUGAUCUACCGUAGUAUCCUAUUUUUAAGUUUAUUUUAUUUUUAAGGAGUAUUGUCAUCACUUUUCAAGGUGUCUUGACUUCUACACAAAGUAUAUAUAUUCAGGACUUUAAAAAAUAGCAGUACACAUUUAACAGUAGCGAAUUACACCAAAAUGAUUUACUUUGAGAUUUGAAUAAUUUGCAUAGCAGUAAAAUGUGUUUUGUGUAACAUACAAAUAGAAAAAUGACCCAGUAUCUUAAUUGAUACUUACUGGAGAGUAUCAGAAUUACCCAGCAGCUCUUACAGAAUGCCAUAAAUUCUUUAAGACUAAAUAUUGAAAUCAAUUAUUUGAAGUAAUGUUUCUGAUUUACUGUUAAAAGUUGCUGAGCUCAGUUUUUGGAGAUAUCAUUUAUGCCUGCCUGUUCCCUUAUGACAGUGAGGCCUUCUUUGGCUCCACCUAGUAUGAUAAUCAUGGGUUCUGUUUUAGUUGAUGAGAAGUGGCUCCUAUGAAUGCCUCUGCUCAAUUUCUUUUUAUUUUACUUUAUUUUAUUUUUAGGGGUCUCGCCAACUCCUGGGCUCAAGUGAUUCUCCUGCUUCCACCUCCCCACAGUGCUGGGAUUACAGGCAUGAGCCACCACGCCUGGCUCUCUGUUCUUUUCAGUGUCUCCGUGCCAUCAGUCAGCAGUGCUUACAUGUUUAGCAUAUUGUCAUGCAGUUUCUCUUCUGUUCCCACGAGAUAUUUUUGGACAAAAAAUUGACAAAAGUACAUGUGUUUUUCCCCACCUAUCCCUUAGAAAACCUAAUGUGUACUGCUAUUUUUAAAACCAAAAAGAGACAGCGUGACGAUGCGUAAAGCAUUUUUCUUAGCCUUUCCUUUGUCUUGAUCUGUUAAUGAGAACAAAACUGCCAGACUCAAAAUACUCUACUAUUGUGCUGAAAGAAAUACAAUUUAGAUUGCACAAAAUUUGAAAAUAUAACUCAGCUGUCUUUUAAAAGAGUUGUGUUGUUAUCUACAAGACUAUUAGCAGUCUUUUUUCAGAGCAAAUUUUAACAGCUAGUUGUGAGUGGUUUAAAAUAUAGAAAAUUAUUAAAAUCUUAGUUUGAGGGGUUUUAUAGUGGGAGAAAAAACAGGACCAAAGUUUAUGUGCCUUCUUCAGUAGUCUUAAUUGACCUUUUCUUCCUAUUUGAGACUAAAGUAGUAUCAGUAUUCUGGUUUUCAGGAAAUAUGUACUAUAUAGUUUUAAAAGAAUGUUGUCCCACCAACUAUUCAUCCAAGCAAAGAAUUGUAACUAUAAAUAAAGUCUCAGUUACACUUUUGCCUUUAUCACAUAAUAUUCAUUGUAGAGCAUUGUGCAGGUCCAAGAAUAGAGCUGCUCAAAAUCUUUGUGGUAGUUUCCUUAGUUUUUGUAACCUGAGGCAUAUGUUCCAGAGAACAGGGAUAUUUGUCUGGUCCAGUGACCUUGGUGAUCAUAGUCAUAAUUGAAAGAUGCCUAUGGCAUGCUUAAAUCAGCAUUGUCAACUGAUUUGUUGUUGUAUUAUUUUCACUUCUUGGAUCUAUGUAGUAGUUGUAAUAACAAAUAUUUAAAUAGCUAUUUUUUUGAUGCCAUUAAAAAAAUCAUACUCUGGCCUUUUUUCCCCCUUACUGUUGUUUCCCAGAUCUUUUAAAAAUUCAUCCCAUAUCCAGAAAGUACCAGUUAUAAAGAUUGCUGACCAAGCAAAGUUUUGCAUCAAAGUGUCACCUCAUUGCUCUGACCAAAGACUGACUGUUGUGGUUUUAACUCCUCUCUGUAAAGCAUUUUGCAUUUUCCCCAAGCUCCUUUCUGAAAGAAGAACCAGUGCAGAGCGGCCUUUACUUUCAAUUUCUACUGCUGAAUAGACUACUUAGAGAAAAUGUGAGUUUCAGUGUGAACAGAAUGGAUUAGGAUGACGAGUUUGAUGGGCAUUUUCAGUACUGUAUCUAAGAAAAAAAAAAUAGCACAGCUAGGAGCCUCUGACAUUGUCUGGUGUUUUACGUGGUCUGUUCAUCAAAAUUCCCCUUUUCAGUUUUUAAGAAUGUUCGUCUAACAGAAGAAAAUGCUGUAAAUAUUUGUAACAACAUUUUUUUUAACAAGGCCAAAAAAGAAAAAAAGGUUUUUGGGAACAAAUGAACUUAUAAAGUGGUUUUAUAUAAAACAUCAAUUGUCUUGUAUAUUUUGGAUAAGCAGCAGUACCAGCUUUCAUUUGUAACAGUCUGUGGCAUUGGAAAAAAAGGAGUCUGUGAUUGUUGAAGUGAAUUAUGUUAUAAAUGCAAAGAGAAGAUAAAAUAUUAAAAAACAUAUUUUCUAAAUGCGUAGUGCAUGGUUAAUUCAAGCUUCUGUACACUACAGUAUAUUCCAUUUUCGUUCAGUUUGUAUAUUUGCUGACUAUUACUUGAUAUCUCUAAUCUCUUUUCCUAACAAAUAUAGCAUUGUAGCAUGCCUUUUAAUAAAUGUCAUGACAUCUGUACUCUCUUAAAAUUUUUCUGUGUUCUUGUCUGUACUUUGGGUUUCCCUUUGUCUUACCUGUAAUUCUAAUGAUGUCCUAUUUUCUUUUCUUUUCCAUAGCCAUCCAUCUAAACGUGUCAUGGUUAGUGAAUAGUGAGCACAUAUUCAAACAAUGUUCAAAAUGGGAAAAACACAAAAUCUAUUAACUGUCUCUGUCUUCAUUUAGGAAUAAUUCUCGUUUUGAGGAGCAAAGUGCUUUCCUAAUCUUCCUAUGAUGCACCUUCUCUGGCACUGCCCCGUAAUGCAGGGGCAUGGCGGCAUGCUUUCUUGCUUGCACACUCACUCUCCUUUUUCUUUCUCUCUUUCUCCCCAUAUGUGCAGUGCCAAACUACAGUUGGAACACUAUUUCCAGUUUUGUUCAGUAUUUGGCUUCCCUACGGCAUUAGUAUACAUACACUUUGAGACACAAGGUGUGAUCUCAAACCAAAUUUGUGUCCUCUUUAAAAAGGUAGCACAGAUACUAGCUGAUGCUACAUUCCUUUUCCUUAGACAAACGUUUUACUUCUCAGAUCUUUAAAGAAUUGUUGGAUUGCAGAAGUCUAGACUUAGCGUUCAUUGUAUAUUUUAGUCUCCUGGAAGUGGGAAUUUAUUUUGAAUGGAAUAGAAAAUUAGGUAAUCACUACUAAUCUUUGCUGGCUUACCUGUAAAAUCUGUGGUCUCCAUAAAUACUGGGAAAAUAAAUAGGUAUUUUUA